ACUUCCGGGUGCGCGGUCCCGAGGUACGCGGUGCGGUCUCCCGGUACCCGGAGCGGCUCUGAUUCAUGGUGAGCCUGCUGGUCGCGGGUUAGCGAGGCGGACAGGAGAGGGAGCCGUGGCUGAAUGGUCUGGGGAGGGAGGAGUGGGUUUAGCAGCUGUGGCUUCCGAGGACCCCACCUAGACCGGUCCUAGCAGGGCUGUGGGGAGGAGCUCCUCGUCCCCGCCCAGGACCAGCUGGUGGGGGCGCUGGCUGCCUGGAAAGCCUUUUCUUCCACUUGGGGCUUUAACAAAUGAAAGCUGGAAGAACAGAUGUUUUGGAAGUUCUUUCGCGUUCCAGAAUAGUUUUUUUUGUGCGUUCCCCAAGCCAAGCCGUCUAUCAGUCUGACCGUGGCCGCCUUUUUUCCCUUUCUCUGAACUGGAGGUCCGAACGCAAGGCUCAUUGAUGGCAAUACGCCCAAGGUGUUGGAAACCUGUGGGAAGCCGAACCUCAUUAGAAGUGUUGGGUAGAAUCAAAUCCAAGGGAAGAAAUAGUCCCCUCGGGCUUUGUUCGGGCUAGAACACACACACAGAAUAGGGAUCUGCUCAUGGUUUAGAAAAACAGUCUUAAAGAACCAUGUAUAAAUAAAAGAGUGUCAGGACAAAGUUGAUUUGGGCCAGGCGCGGUGGCUCACGCCUGUAAUCCCAGCAGUUCGGGAGGCCGAGGCCGGCGGAUCACUUGAGGUCAGGAGUUCGAGACCAGCCUGGCCAAACCCUGUCCCCACGAAAAAUACAAAAAUUAGCUGGGUGUGGUGGAGCGCGCCUGUAAUCCCAGCUACUCAGGAGGCUGAGGCAGGAGAAUCGCUUGAACCCACCAGGUGGAGGUUGCACUGAACCGAGAUCACGCCACUGCACUCCAGCCUGGGCGACAGAGCAACACUUGGUCUCACAAAAAAAAAGAACGUUGAUUUGAUGGGUGAGGUACUUGGAAACCCACGAAAUCUAAGGAACAGUUGAGCUGUGGAGAGGAAAAGAAUUAAGAGGCAAGAUAAUUGUUUUCAAGUGUUGGAAGGCUGCUAUGGAGAAAUAGAGACGGGGUUUCACCGUGUUAGCCAGAAUGGUCUCGAUCUCCUGACCUCGUGAUCUGCCCGCCUCGGGCCUCCCAAAGUGCUGGAAUUACAGGUGUGAGCCACGGCGCCGGGCCCCCUAGGGAUUUUCAGGUACGGACUGAGUGUGAAGCAUUUUAGCACAAGUGGGUUUAACUUGUGGCCCUAAAGAACUGGAAACCCAAAGGAACGAAUAUUCCUGCCCCACAGAGUCCCAUCUUUGGUGAGGCUGUUUCUGGAGUUUACAUGAUGACCAAGGUACUAGGCAUGGCCCCAGUUCUGGGCCCUAGGCCUCCACAGGAGCAGGUGGGGCCUCUGAUGGUAAAAGUCGAGGAGAAAGAAGAGAAAGGCAAGUACCUUCCUAGCCUGGAGAUGUUCCGCCAGCGCUUCAGGCAGUUUGGGUACCAUGAUACCCCUGGACCCCGAGAGGCCCUGAGCCAACUCCGGGUGCUCUGCUGUGAGUGGCUGAGGCCCGAGAUCCACACCAAGGAGCAGAUCCUGGAGCUACUGGUGCUGGAGCAGUUCCUGACCAUCCUGCCCCAGGAGCUCCAGGCCUGGGUGCAGGAGCAUUGCCCGGAGAGCGCUGAAGAGGCUGUCACUCUCCUCGAAGAUCUGGAGCGGGAACUGGAUGAGCCAGGACACCAGGUCUCAACUCCUCCAAACGAACAGAAACCGGUGUGGGAGAAGAUAUCCUCCUCAGGAACUGCAAAGGAAUCCCCGAGCAGCAUGCAGCCACAGCCCUUGGAGACCAGUCACAAAUACGAGUCUUGGGGGCCCCUGUACAUCCAAGAGUCUGGUGAGGAGCAGGAGUUCGCUCAAGAUCCAAGAAAGGUCCGAGAUUGCAGAUUGAGUACCCAGCACGAGGAAUCAGCAGAUGAGCAGAAAGGUUCUGAAGCAGAGGGGCUCAAAGGGGAUAUAAUUUCUGUGAUUAUCGCCAAUAAACCUGAGGCCAGCUUAGAGAGGCAGUGCGUAAACCUUGAAAAUGAAAAAGGAACAAAACCCCCUCUUCAAGAGGCAGGCUCCAAGAAAGGUAGAGAAUCAGUUCCUACUAAACCUACCCCAGGAGAGAGACGUUAUAUAUGUGCUGAAUGUGGCAAAGCCUUUAGUAAUAGCUCAAAUCUCACCAAACACAGGAGAACACACACUGGGGAGAAACCUUACGUGUGCACCAAGUGUGGGAAAGCUUUCAGCCACAGCUCAAACCUCACCCUCCACUACAGAACACACUUGGUGGACCGGCCCUAUGACUGUAAGUGUGGAAAAGCUUUUGGGCAGAGCUCAGACCUUCUUAAACAUCAGAGAAUGCACACAGAAGAGGCGCCAUAUCAGUGCAAAGAUUGUGGCAAGGCUUUCAGCGGGAAAGGCAGCCUCAUUCGUCACUAUCGGAUCCACACUGGGGAGAAGCCUUAUCAGUGUAACGAAUGUGGGAAGAGCUUCAGUCAGCAUGCGGGCCUCAGCUCCCACCAGAGACUCCACACCGGAGAGAAGCCAUAUAAGUGUAAGGAGUGUGGGAAAGCCUUCAACCACAGCUCCAACUUCAAUAAACACCACAGAAUCCACACCGGGGAAAAGCCCUACUGGUGUCAUCACUGUGGAAAGACCUUCUGUAGCAAGUCCAAUCUUUCCAAACAUCAGCGAGUCCACACUGGAGAGGGAGAAGCACCGUAACUUUCAAGCGCUCCUGUUGUUGUCGUUGUUUUAAACUUUAGAAUCUGAAAACCAGAAAGAAGUCUUGUCAUUGCAGCAGCAUCGAUUCCGGUGAUAGAGUUUGUAUCACUCAACAUCAGGGGAUGCCUGAGGAGUGCGAGCUCCACAGCAACAUGGCAGGCAGGAGGUCCUCAGAAGGUGUCAGGAGGUUCCACACUCGCCAGUUCACUGGAGCAGAGUCCCUUCGCCACACUUAGGGUCCCAGUAAGCCAUGCCAGCAUUACCUUUUGCGUAGUUAAACAGACGUGUAUCCAGUCUAGUUAAGGAAGAAACAUUAAGAUUGUUUAAUUUUUAACAUAUAUUCAAGAAUUUUAAUUUGUAAAGAAUUGAGCCACAUUGAACACAAUUGAAUGAGAUUCAGAAUAAACUUAUAACAUCUUGUAA